GCGCGCCGCUGGCCGACGGAGGGGAGCCUGCCGAUGCCGAGCGGGUGCUACGUCCCGCGGUCGGAGCCGCGUCUUCUCCCGGCUCCGCCACCAGCCGGGGCUCGGGUGGGGGCCCGGGGCCCCGGGGCAUGGCCCUCCGGAGUGCGCAGGGCGACGGCCCCACCUCCGGCCACUGGGACGGCGGCGCGGAGAAGGCAGACUUUAACGCCAAAAGGAAAAAGAAAGUGGCAGAGAUACACCAGGCUCUGAACAGUGAUCCCACUGAUGUGGCUGCCCUUAGACGCAUGGCUAUCAGUGAAGGAGGGCUCCUGACUGAUGAGAUCAGACGAAAAGUGUGGCCCAAGCUCCUCAAUGUCAAUGCCAAUGACCCACCUCCUAUAUCAGGGAAGAACCUACGGCAGAUGAGCAAGGACUACCAACAAGUGUUGCUGGACGUCCGGCGGUCAUUGCGGCGGUUCCCUCCUGGCAUGCCAGAGGAACAGAGAGAAGGGCUCCAGGAAGAACUGAUUGACAUCAUCCUCCUCAUCUUGGAGCGCAACCCUCAGCUGCACUACUACCAGGGCUACCAUGACAUUGUGGUCACAUUUCUGCUGGUGGUAGGCGAGAGGCUGGCAACAUCCCUGGUAGAAAAAUUAUCUACCCACCACCUCAGGGAUUUUAUGGAUCCAACAAUGGACAACACCAAGCAUAUAUUAAACUAUCUGAUGCCCAUCAUUGACCAGGUGAAUCCAGAGCUCCAUGACUUCAUGCAGAGUGCUGAGGUAGGGACCAUCUUUGCCCUCAGCUGGCUCAUCACCUGGUUUGGGCAUGUCCUGUCUGACUUCAGGCACGUCGUGCGGUUAUAUGACUUCUUCCUGGCCUGCCACCCACUGAUGCCGAUUUACUUUGCAGCCGUGAUUGUGUUGUAUCGCGAGCAGGAAGUCCUGGACUGUGACUGUGACAUGGCCUCGGUCCACCACCUGUUGUCCCAGAUCCCUCAGGACUUGCCCUAUGAGACACUGAUCAGCAGAGCAGGAGACCUUUUUGUUCAGUUUCCCCCAUCCGAACUUGCUCGGGAGGCCGCUGCCCAACAGCAAGCUGAGAGGACGGCAGCCUCUACUUUCAAAGACUUUGAGCUGGCAUCAGCCCAGCAGAGGCCUGAUAUGGUGCUGCGGCAGCGGUUUCGGGGACUUCUGCGGCCUGAAGAUCGAACAAAAGAUGUCCUGACCAAGCCAAGGACCAACCGCUUUGUGAAAUUGGCAGUGAUGGGGCUGACAGUGGCACUUGGAGCGGCUGCACUGGCUGUGGUGAAAAGUGCCCUGGAAUGGGCCCCUAAGUUUCAGCUGCAGCUGUUUCCCUGAAAGCCAGAGAAGACCUUCCUCUUACAUCACAUUAAGGUCUCACCCUUCCAUGGAAGGAUUGGGAGGGGUGGAAUUUCCUUUAUUAAAAGGGUUUCUGUCCAGAGUUUUUUAUUCCUGCCACCCUGCCCUGCCCGUUUGUGUUUGCCUUUACUUCAGAGGCCAGUAGCAGAGCCUACCUGACACAGAGGGGACCUGGGGGCCUGGCACAGAAUCUUAUGCCUCUCCCAGUGGGCUUUUGGAUGGGCUCUCUGCCACCUCCCUGGUGUUGGAGGAAGUGGGUUUCUGAAGCUUGCAGCUGCUUUUGCAACCUGCUGGGCCUGGGCUGCCCUAGUUACCGGGAACCUCCUAGUCACCCCAUAGAAGGUGAACUGGAACAUGGGAUGCCCUCUUACUGCUCCUGCUUGCCUGCAUCAGAUGGACACAGAAGGAGGGGGCUGCUGCUGAAGGAGUCAGGCUUGGGAUGGAGAGCAAGAGGCCAAAGGACUCGUCUGGGAGCAUGAUCGGCCCCUCUUACUAGCAGCUCCAUCAGCUGAUCAGAAAUCAGAGACAGAAGGGAACUAGGUUACUCGUUAAAUCCUACCUAUUUUCAGCCUAGAAAUCACAUGGGCGUUUCCAGUCAAGUGGGAAGGAAGCUCAUUUUUAGGGCCUAGACCUAGACUAGUUUUGCCUGCCUUUUUUUCCUCCCUGCUUUCUUCUACAAGCCACACAACAUUGCUUAUAAAAGGUACUUUUAUUACUAUUUUUAGAAUAUAUACACCCCAUAUGUAAAUUACCCUCACUUUUAAAGUAAUAAUAGUUCCUUCACGGAAAAAAAAAUAGUUCUCAUCAGAAGGAUGAGCUUCUAAGAUCCUGAAUUUUACUUUCUACUUGAUUAACAUUUUCGCUUUAGCCAGAGUUGCUAUUUGCAAACAGCUUUCCACUUCCAAAGUGCCACUUUCUGACCGGUUUUUCUUCCUGUUUUCCUCAAAUCAUCCUACUCCCAAAUAGGCACCCACUCACUACCUUGGCGUCGUUUUUUGGGUCUGACUUGACUCGUCAACUGCUGGUCUCUCCCACCUGGUUGGAAAUGUCGUUGGAAACUUGCAAAGACUCUCCAGACCUUAGGGAACAAGAGGCAUCACUCAGUCCUUCUGGGACAGCUUCCCUGUAAGCAAAGCCAGGUUUGUUUUAGAUUCACUCUGGCCUGAAAAAAAAAGUGCCUUUUGCUGCUUUAAAGAAUUGGGGUAUAUGGUAUGAAGCAGCCAUGUACUUGUAUUUUCCUGGUCUUUCCUGGGCACUCUUCUCUCUUGGCAGAUGUUUUCUUAAAGUGAACACACCAGAAGCACUCUACCCCACCAUAUCCAGUCCUCUUUGCAUGCCUGUUGUGUGCAGGGUGGAGGGUGUCCCACGUGCCAGAGCAGCUGGGAGCCCUGUCCGCUGAGUUACACUAAGCACUUUAUUUUUAUUUAUUUUAUUAUUAUUUUCUUUUUUCUGAGAUGGAGUCUCACUCUGUUGCCCAGGCUGGAGUGCAGUGGUGCAGUCUCAGCUCACUGCAACCUCCGCCUCCCAAGUUCAGGCAAUUCUCGCUGCCUCAGCCUCCCGAGUAGCUGGGACUACAGGCACCUGCUACCACGCCUGACUAAUUUUUGUAUUUUUAGUAGAGAUGGGGUUUCGCCACGUUGGCCAGGCUGGUCUCGAACUCCUGACCUCAGGUGAUCUGCCCGUCUCGUCCUCCCAAAGUGCUGGGAUUACAGGUGUGAGCCACCACGCCCAGCCACCACUACGCACUUUAAAACCAAAAAAAGCUCAAAGGGAUGGAUCAUUGUCCAUGGCUCAGGAGCCCCACUGUGGGGUAAGUGUGAUGUCGAUGGAUUAAUUUAGACAGUGGUGUAUUCAUCAGGGCAAAGGAAAUUCUUCCAGAGGUGAUGAUGCGGCAGAUAUUCCCAGUGCUCUCCCAAAGCAAGCUGGCCCUCUUGUCAUCCUCUCAGUGGGCGGCACCAGCUGCCCCUCCUUCCACAAGUACUCAAGCCUGUUUGUAAAUACUGAAGGAAUUGAUGGGGUUGAGGAAAGGAGGUGCAUGUGACCAGGGUCCCAAGGCCACAGCUUUUCAGAUCCUAGGAAGCAAGUGGCAUUUGCUUGAGUUGUGGCCUCGGAAGGAGAAUGUUUAUCUGUUUUCUAACUUUGCUGACACCAGGAUUCUCCCUGUCAUUGAGAAGAAAGCAUUAUCUAAUUACCUUCAGGUGGUUUACUUAUUCUGUAAAGAAUAUGUGUAAAUAUUUUGUACAGAGCCCUGUAUCAAAUAAACAGCCAUAUGUGGUUACUAAUCACCUCUUCUGUCAUUCCGUCCUUGGCCACCGCUCAGUGGGAAUGGUCUCUGAUCUGGAUGCUCCCACCUUCCAUGUCAGGCCCAGAACUGUGCCAUGGUCUGUGGACUCCUGGUCAGCCUUGACUGGCUAGGAGACCUUGGGCAGUACCUACAGUCUUGCUGUUUCUGUUUCAUCUGCAAGAAUUAUGACCCACACACUCCAGCUGCAGCCCAGGGCACUGUGAUAUUUUAUACGUGUGUAGAUGUUUUUGUCCACAGUUCCUGGUUCAUCACUCCCAUAACCCUUUGUUAUAAUGUUGGGACACUGCAGGCCUCAGAAAACGGAAUCUCUGUCUGUGACCUUCUCCUGCCCCAUUUCACUUGCUCAACACCAGACUUUAAUCUGACUGUAGCUCAUAAGACCCUCAUUCCAGAGAGGGUGCUGCCCCAUACCCGGAAGGAGGAACGCUGCACAGAGAGGCCAAGAAGCAUCUGGACAGACAGGCCUUGCUGGGUUUAGACCUUAUGCUUUUUGUCCAGUUUCAUCUCAACACAGCUGCCAUGCUUCAGCCAUGCCUAUCCAAUGACGUCUCCAUAAAAGGCCCAGGAACACGGGAGCUUCUGAAGAGCUGAACAUGUGGAGGGAGGGGAACGAGAACUUGUCCAUGUGCCAAGAGGGUGGCGCACCCCCACUCCAUGGGGACAGAAGCUCCAGCAUUUGCCCAGGACCCGUCCAGACCUCACCCUGUGUGUAUCUUCAUCUGGCUGUUUACUUAUUUGUAUCCUUUUCUAAUAAUGUUUGUAAUAAACUGGUAAACAUAA